AUUGGGUAUAUUAACGUGCUGUGGAUUGGGUUAAGCUUAUGAAAUCUAAGACAGUUAAGUCUGAUUUGUAAUAAUACCUUAGAAGCCCAAGUUUCAUUAGCAUUUGUAUUUUUGCUGGUACAGAAACUUUGUGUUUUAUAUGAAGUUGACUUGGAUUGUUAGAGAAAAAAUAUUCAUAAACAGUUUAAGUAAUAUUGUUGCUUUAUCAUAUUGCAGUUUGACGUUGAAAAUUGUAAAGUUUUAAUCUGCACAGUCCUGCACUAUUUUUGUGAUUCUGUUUUUAUCUUGAUUUAUUCCGGUUGCUGCCUUUUAAAGUGGGGGGGGGAGGGGUAAAAAAAAAACAACUCUGGUGUCUUUACCAAGUCUGUUUCAGAGCUUUUUGAUUCAUUUGAUCUUUUUGGAACACUUUACCUCCUUUACGUUUCUAUCUGUGUUCACUUUUGCACAUUGUGUAACUUCGUGCUGACUAAAUGAGGGCCAGAGAGAGAAAGAUAAACUUAUCAGCAUUUUUAUUUUAAUACGUUAGAGUGGAGGAAUGUGUAUGCGAGGGUGGAGAUUACGGGUAAGUUGAGAAAGGAAAUAGUAACAUUCCAGAUUUUUCCUACUUCUAACCUUAUUCUCAGUUUUAAACAUUACUGAGUUUACUCAGCAUUUAUACAGAGGAAUCAAUCAUCCGAAGGUUUCCUGUUUUAUAAUGGGUUUGUAAAACACUAUCUUGACUUAAUCUGUGAUCAUUGCAAAAAUUGUUUAAAGACUUUCAUUACUGGUUGUAAUUCACAUAGUGUGAUGAUUUUUAAUUUCGUUAUUAUAUAUGAAACUUAAAAGUAAUGACAGUUAUUUGGAAGACAAUCAGAAUUACUUUUAUAGAACACUUAGGUCCAGAAUAGGUCUUUCUCAAAUGUCAUGAUGUAAAAGGGGCAAGGAAUGUACAUUUAGGUGAGAAACAGCAGCUUCUGAUGCUAGUUCCCUGAAAAACCUUACUUCUGCAACCAAAAGUUGGGUUAGGAGUAUUUCAGGAUUGUUUCGGAGAAAAUCAUGUAGGCGCCAGGCGUGGUGGCUCACGCCUGUAAUCCCAACACUUUGAGAGGCCGAGGCGGUGGAUCACUUGAGAUCAGGAGUUCCAGACCAGCUUGGCCAACAUGGUGAAACCUUGUCUCUACUAAAAAUAAAAAAGUUAGCCAGGCGUGGUGUUGGGUGCUUGUAUUUCCAGCUACCCGGGAGGCUGAGGCAGGAGAACCGAUUGAACUCGGGAGGCAGAGUUGUAGUGAGCAGAGAUUGCACCACUGCACUCCAUCCUGGGCGGUAAAGCGAGACUCCGUUUCAAAAAAAAAAAAAAAAGGAAAAUUAUAUAGAUAUUUAACUUUUUAAAAGCCAGCAAAUGGUUCUUCCAAGAAGGUUAGAAAACCUCUGCCCACGGUGUUUCUUAAUCCAUGGAUUUGUGGUCUAUUUUGAAUCCAAAAGCCAGAAAGGCUAUUUAAGCAUAUAUAUGUGUAUGGUUUUUAUUUAUUUAUUUAUUUAUUUUUGAGACAGAGUCUCGCUCUGUCGCCCAGGCUGGAGUGCAGUGGUGUGAUCUCGGCUCACUGCAAGCUCCGCCUCCCGGGUUCACGCCAUUCGGCCUCAGUCUCCCGAGUAGCUGGGACUACAGGCGCCCGCCACCACGCCCGGCUAAUUUUUUAUAUUUUUAGUAGAGACAGGGUUUCAUCAUGUUAGCCAGGAUGGUCUCGAUCUCCUGACUCCGUGAUCCGCCCACCUCGGCCUCCCAAAGUGCUGGGAUUACAGGCAUGAGCCACCGUGCCCAGCCAAUGUGGAUGGUUUUUAAAUUUUUUUAAUUAAAAAAAAUUUUUAUUAAAUUUAUUUAAAAAAAUUUUUUUUUGGGGAGACGAAGUCUUGCUAUGUUGCCCAGGCUGAUCUUGAACUUGUAGCUUCAAGAGAUCCUCCUUCCUUAGACUCCCAAAGUGCUGGGAUUUAUAGGCGAGAGCCACCAGUUUAUAUGUGUUUUUUAAAGGUACAAAGAUGAAACCUGUAGUUUGUAUUAGGGAAACAAAUGAAAAUAAGUAGUUGCAGUUUAGUAUAAAAAGUUGAAACUGAAGUAUGUAUAUAAAAAAGUACUAUGGGAGCUCAAAGGUUUUUCUUAAAAUUUUUAUUCUGUAUUAGAAAAGGGGGAGGUGAGUGGGCUUUCUGCUUUUGUCCUCUUUCUGCGUGUUUAUUCAAUACUAUUUUGGGCCUCUACCAUAGACCUUUAUUAAUUGGUAAGCUUGCAUGUUUUUAUUAGUAAACUGGCAUAUGAUGUUGCAAAAAAAAAAAAGUACCAGAAAAUAUCCAGUCUGCUUGUGUGACUUUGAUUUCCGUAGUAACUUGUCAUAAAUAAGAUAUCUUGUUGUUUUUCUUUUCACAGAUGCUGCACUUAAAAGGAUGCUUGUUUUGAUGUCCUGCUCAUUGUUUUCCCUAUGAACCAAAAGUUUUGGAAGGUCUCCAUCAAGAAAACAAAAUUAUUCAUCAAAAAAUGAAAACUGUGUGGAAGAAACUUUUGAAGAUUUGCUUUUAAAGUAUAAACAAAUACAGUUGGAACUAGAAUGCAUCAAUAAGGAUGAAAAACUAGCAUUGAGUAGCAAAGAAGAGAAUGUGCAGGAAGAUCCUAAAACAUUGAACUUCGAGGACCAAACUAGCACUGAUAAUGUCAGUAUUACAAAGGAUUCAAGUAAAGAAGUAGCUCCUGAGGAGAAAACACAAGUCAAAACUUUUCAGGCAUUUGAAUUAAAACCACUCAGGCAAAAAUUGACUUUACCAGGAGAUAAGAACCGUUUGAAAAAAGUUAAAGAUGGAGCAAAACCACUUUCCCUGAAAUCCGACACUACUGAUUCUAGUCAAGGAUUACAAGAUAAAGAACAAAAUUUAACAAGAAGAAUUAGUACCUCAGAUAUUCUGUCUGAAAAGAAACUUGGUGAAGAUGAAGAGGAACUAUCUGAAUUACAGCUUCGCCUUUUGGCUCUUCAGUCAGCCAGUAAAAAAUGGCAACAAAAAGAACAGCAGGUGAUGAAAGAAAGCAAAGAAAAGUUGACUAAGACGAAAACUGUACAGCAAAAAGUUAAAACAAGUACAAAAACACAUUCGGCCAAAAAAGUUAGCACUACAGCUAAACAAGCAUUGAGGAAGCAGCAAACAAAGGCAUGGAAGAAACUACAACAACAAAAAGAGCAGGAAAGACAGAAAGAAGAGGAUCAGCGGAAACAAGCUGAAGAAGAAGAGAGAAGGAAAAGAGAGGAAGAAAUCAGAAAAAUUCGAGAUCUCUCAAAUCAGGAAGAACAGUACAAUCGAUUCAUGAAAUUGGUUGGUGGCAAGAGGAGAUCAAGAAGUAAAUCUUCAGAUCCUGACCUGAGGCGAUCCUUAGAUAAGCAACCUACUGAUAGUGGAGGAGGCAUUUAUCAGUAUGAUAACUAUGAAGAAGUUGCUAUGGAUACAGAUAGUGAAACCAGUUCUCCAGCUCCUUCACCAGUGCAACCGCCAUUUUUCUCUGAAUGUUCAUUGGGGUAUUUUUCUCCAGCACCAUCUCUUUCUUUGCCUCCACCACCUCAGGUUUCUUCUCUGCCACCUUUGAGCCAGCCUUAUGUGGAAGGCUUGUGUGUUUCUCUUGAACCUCUACCUCCUCUACCACCAUUACCACCUCUCCCACCUGAAGAUCCAGAACAGCCUCCAAAACCACCUUUUGCAGAUGAGGAAGAGGAGGAAGAAAUGCUGCUUCGAGAAGAACUACUUAAAUCUCUAGCAAAUAAAAGAGCUUUUAAGCCAGAGGAAACAUCCAGUAAUAGUGACCCACCUUCACCUCCAGUUCUGAACAAUUCACAUCCUGUGCCAAGAAGCAAUCUAUCAAUAGUCAGUAUUAACACAGUGUCUCAGCCUAGGAUACAGAAUCCAAAGUUUCACAGAGGACCCCGUCUUCCACGAACUGUGAUCUCGCUUCCAAAGCAUAAAUCAGUGGUUGUAACACUAAAUGAUUCAGAUGAUAGUGAAUCUGAUGGAGAGGCUUCCAAGUCAACAAAUAGUGUUUUUGGUGGAUUAGAGUCCAUGAUUAAAGAAGCAAGACGAACUGCUGAGCAAGCUUCAAAACCGAAAGUACCUCCAAAAUCUGAAAAAGAAAAUGAUCCUCUGCGAACACCGGAGGCUUUGCCUGAAGAAAAGAAGAUUGAAUAUAGAUUGUUAAAGGAAGAGAUUGCCAACCGUGAGAAACAGCGUUUGAUUAAAUCAGAUCAGCUGAAGACAAGUUCAUCAUCCCCAGCAAACUCUGAUGUGGAAAUUGAUGGUAUUGGCAGGAUAGCAAUGGUUACUAAGCAGGUUACAGAUGCAGAAUCAAAACUGAAAAAACAUAGGAUUCUCUUGAUGAAAGAUGAAUCUGUUUUAAAGAAUUUAGUGCAACAAGAAGCUAAGAAGAAAGAAUCUGUUAGAAAUGCUGAAGCAAAGAUUACAAAACUUACAGAACAGCUUCAAGCAACUGAAAAAAUUCUUAAUGUUAACAGAAUGUUUUUGAAGAAGCUUCAGGAACAAAUUCACAGAGUUCAACAGCGUGUUACAAUUAAGAAAGCUUUGACUCUAAAAUAUGGAGAAGAGCUUGCUCGGGCAAAGGCAGUGGCCAGUAAAGAAAUAGGAAAACGUAAACUGGAACAAGAUCGCUUUGGGCCAAACAAAAUGAUGAGACUGGACAGUUCUCCAGUAUCAAGUCCAAGAAAGCAUUCAGCAGAACUAAUUGCUAUGGAGAAAAGACGGUUACAAAAGCUAGAAUAUGAAUAUGCCCUGAAAAUUCAAAAAUUAAAAGAAGCCCGUGCCCUUAAAGCAAAGGAACAACAAAAUAUCUCUCCAGUUGUGGAAGAGGAACCCGAAUUUUCUUUACCUCAACCCUCACUUCAUGAUCUGACACAAGAUAAAUUAACCCUGGACACUGAAGAAAAUGAUGUUGAUGAUGAAAUUUUGUCUGGUUCAAGCAGAGAGCGAAGAAGAUCUUUUUUAGAAUCCAAUUAUUUUACUAAACCUAACCUUAAGCACACUGAUACUGCUAACAAAGAAUGCAUAAACAAACUUAAUAAAAAUACUGUAGAAAAACCAGAACUUUUUCUAGGGUUAAAAAUUGGUGAAUUGCAAAAAUUGUAUUCAAAAGCUGACAGCCUAAAACAGCUGAUUUUAAAAACCACCACAGGCAUUACAGAGAAGGUUUUGCAUGGUCAGGAGAUUUCUGUAGAUGUGGAUUUUGUCACAGCACAAAGUAAAACAAUGGAAGUGAAGCCAUGUCCUUUUAGACCCUACCAUAGUCCUCUUCUAGUUUUUAAGUCCUACAGAUUUAGUCCAUAUUAUCGAACCAAGGAAAAACUUCCCCUGAGCUCAGUAUCAUACAGUAAUAUGAUUGAACCGGAUCAGUGUUUCUGCCGUUUUGAUUUAACAGGAACAUGUAAUGAUGAUGAUUGUCAAUGGCAGCAUAUACAAGACUAUACACUUAGCCGAAAACAGUUAUUCCAGGACAUUCUGUCAUAUAAUCUGUCUUUGAUUGGUUGUGCAGAGACAAGUACUAAUGAAGAAAUUACUGCUUCAGCAGAAAAAUAUGUUGAGAAACUUUUUGGAGUAAACAAAGAUCGAAUGUCAAUGGACCAGAUGGCUGUUCUCCUUGUUAGCAAUAUCAAUGAAAGUAAAGGUCAUACUCCUCCAUUUACAACCUACAAAGAUAAAAGAAAGUGGAAGCCAAAGUUUUGGAGAAAACCUAUUUCAGAUAAUAGCUUCAGUAGUGAUGAGGAACAGUCUACAGGACCAAUUAAGUAUGCUUUCCAGCCAGAGAACCAAAUAAAUGUUCCAGCUCUGGAUACAGUUGUCACUCCAGAUGAUGUCAGAUACUUUACAAAUGAGACUGAUGACAUCGCUAAUUUAGAAGCAAGUGUGCUUGAAAAUCCUUCUCAUGUACAACUUUGGCUCAAGCUUGCGUACAAGUACUUGAAUCAAAAUGAGGGGGAGUGCUCAGAAUCCUUGGAUUCUGCUUUAAAUGUUCUGGCGCGAGCAUUGGAAAAUAACAAAGACAAUCCAGAAAUUUGGUGCCAUUACCUCAGAUUGUUCUCAAAAAGAGGAACCAAGGACGAGGUGCAGGAAAUGUGUGAAACAGCUGUUGAAUAUGCUCCAGAUUAUCAAAGCUUUUGGACUUUUCUACACCUAGAAAGUACCUUUGAAGAAAAGGAUUACGUAUGUGAGAGAAUGUUGGAGUUUCUGAUGGGAGCAGCCAAGCAGGAAACAUCCAAUAUUUUGUCCUUUCAGCUUUUAGAGGCUCUUUUGUUUAGAGUUCAGCUGCACAUAUUUACUGGAAGAUGCCAAAGUGCACUGGCAAUUUUACAGAAUGCAUUGAAAUCUGCUAAUGAUGGAAUAGUAGCUGAAUACCUUAAAACCAGUGAUCGAUGUUUGGCAUGGUUGGCCUACAUACAUCUUAUUGAAUUCAACAUUCUCCCUUCAAAAUUUUAUGAUCCAUCUAAUGAUAAUCCUUCAAGAAUUGUUAACACUGAAUCAUUUGUAAUGCCAUGGCAAGCUGUUCAAGAUGUAAAGACUAAUCCUGACAUGUUGUUAGCAGUUUUUGAAGAUGCAGUGAAAGCUUGCACAGAUGAGAGCCUUGCUGUUGAGGAAAGAAUAGAGGCCUGCCUUCCACUUUACACAAACAUGAUUGCUCUGCACCAACUCCUGGAGAGGUAUGAGGCUGCAAUGGAGCUUUGUAAAUCUUUAUUGGAAUCAUGUCCUAUUAACUGCCAGUUGCUGGAAGCUCUUGUUGCAUUAUAUUUGCAAACAAAUCAGCAUGACAAAGCCAGAGCAGUGUGGCUUACUGCAUUUGAAAAAAAUCCUCAGAAUGCAGAGGUUUUUUAUCAUAUGUGCAAAUUCUUCAUCUUACAGAAUCGAGGCGAUAAUCUUCUUCCAUUUUUGCGGAAAUUUAUUGCAUCCUUCUUUAAACCGGGGUUUGAGAAGUAUAAUAACUUGGAUCUGUUUCGGUAUCUCUUAAAUAUUCCAGGACCAAUUGACAUUCCAUCUCGUUUAUGUAAAGGGAAUUUUGAUGAUGAUAUGUUUAACCACCAAGUUCCUUAUUUGUGGCUGAUUUACUGCCUUUGUCAUCCUCUUCAAUCAAGUAUUAAAGAAACAGUGGAGGCAUAUGAGGCAGCAUUAGGGGUGGCUAUGAGAUGUGAUAUAGUACAGAAGAUAUGGAUGGAUUAUCUUGUCUUUGCAAAUAAUAGAGCUGCUGGAUCCAGAAACAAAGUUCAAGAAUUCAAAUUUUUUACUGAUUUAGUGAAUAGAUGUUUGGUUACAGUCCCUGCCCGAUACCCCAUUCCUUUUAGCAGUGCUGAUUACUGGUCCAACUAUGAAUUUCAUAAUAGGGUUAUUUUCUUUUAUUUGAGCUGUGUUCCAAAGACCCAGCAUUCCAAAACCUUGGAACGGUUUUGUUCAGUUAUGCCAGCUAAUUCUGGACUUGCAUUGAGGUUACUUCAACAUGAAUGGGAAGAAAGCAAUGUUCAGAUUCUGAAACUUCAAGCCAAGAUGUUUACAUAUAAUAUCCCAACAUGCCUGGCCACCUGGAAAAUAGCCAUUGCUGCUGAGAUUGUUCUAAAGGGACAAAGAGAGGUCCACCGUUUAUAUCAGAGAGCCUUACAGAAGUUACCUCUUUGUGCAUCACUGUGGAAAGAUCAACUCUUGUUUGAAGCAUCAGAAGGAGGUAAAACUGAUAACCUGAGAAAACUAGUUUCCAAGUGCCAAGAGAUUGGAGUCAGCCUAAAUGAGCUCUUAAAUUUAAACAGUAACAAAACAGAAAGCAAGAAUCACUGAACACUGGGUGCAGUCAGUUCUAAGUCCUUAUAAUAAUUGCCAAAAUUAUUUGAAUGAUUCUUCAAGAUUAGGCUGAUCCCUGGCUAAGGUCUGUGUAAGGCAGACAAGCGUUAUUGAUCAUAUCAAGUUCCCUACAAUAUCCUGUCCUCAAAACCGGAAGCAAUGAACAUGAUCCUCUUCGGUUGGAUAAAUGAACUUCCUGUUUGGCCUGCUUCUAGGCCCUGCCAGAUUCUCAUAACAUCAUAUACGUAAGUAUAGUUCCUCAAAGUGACUGACAUUUAUUUUAAUUUUGCUUUGUUUUUUUUUAUUUUCUCCCCCAUUCCUUUAUUUUGUGUUAUUCCUGACUCACUUGACACUCUCUGAUGCCUGAGAGAUUCCUGUUUGGGAUUUAAUAUCCAGGGCUGUGUUUACAGUAAAAAAAGCAGGCAGUCCCUUUUAGUUUUUCCUUUUUAAAUUUUUUUGAGAUUCUUCAUUUCAGGAUUUAAAACUAUAGCAGUCCAUCUUAAGGAAAGUGUAACUGCCAUGGCCACAAGUCUGCUAGUUGCACUUGAAUGCUCUAUCAGGGUUGUUUAUUACCCUUUCUACGUUCUGGACUCCUUGCCGAGACUGUUUAACUUGAAGAUUAAAGAAACUAUUGCAAAUGCCAGUGCAUCAGAACCUAAGAGUGGUCAAAUAUUAUGUGCAAUUUUUUUGUAAAGAAAUUUUAAUUUAUAAUAAAGUUUAACAGUUUAAAGAACAGUUAAUAUUUGAACUGCUUUGUAUUGAAAUACUACUUUGUAGUAUUGAAAUUGUUUAUAUACUUUUUUAAUAUAAGUUAACUUUCUAAAAA